CUCUCGGCCGCUCUUCGGGCCGCCUCUGCGUGUGGGGCCGCCCGCGCCAGUGUGAGCCUGAGCUGACGGCGGCUCCGGGAGGCUCGCAGAAGGGGAGGGCCGGGCGGCGCGGGAGCUGAGCAUCGCCAGGGCGGGCGGCAGGGCGCGGCCUCUCCGCCGGGUGUACCACCUGUCGCGGCGCGAGACCUCUGGUGAAAGAAAAGAUGUUGUCCCGGUUAAGAGUAGUUUCCACCACUUGUACUUUGGCAUGUCGACAUUUGCACAUAAAAGAAAAAGGCAAGCCACUUAUGCUGAACCCAAGAACAAACAAGGGAAUGGCAUUUACUUUACAAGAACGACAAAUGCUUGGUCUUCAAGGACUUCUACCUCCCAAAAUAGAGACACAAGAUAUUCAAGCCUUACGAUUUCAUAGAAACUUGAAGAAAAUGACUAGCCCUUUGGAAAAAUAUAUCUACAUAAUGGGAAUACAAGAAAGAAAUGAGAAAUUGUUUUAUAGAAUACUGCAAGAUGACAUUGAGAGUUUAAUGCCAAUUGUAUAUACACCGACGGUUGGUCUUGCCUGCUCCCAGUAUGGACACAUCUUUAGAAGACCUAAGGGAUUAUUUAUUUCGAUCUCAGACAGAGGUCAUGUUAGAUCAAUUGUGGAUAACUGGCCAGAAAAUCAUGUUAAGGCUGUUGUAGUGACUGAUGGAGAGAGAAUUCUGGGUCUUGGAGAUCUGGGUGUCUAUGGAAUGGGAAUUCCAGUAGGAAAACUUUGUUUGUAUACAGCUUGUGCAGGAAUACGGCCUGAUAGAUGCCUGCCAGUGUGUAUUGAUGUGGGAACUGAUAAUAUCGCACUCUUAAAAGACCCAUUUUACAUGGGCUUGUACCAGAAACGAGAUCGCACACAACAGUAUGAUGACCUGAUUGAUGAGUUUAUGAAAGCUAUUACUGACAGAUAUGGCCGGAACACACUCAUUCAGUUCGAAGACUUUGGAAAUCAUAAUGCAUUCAGGUUCUUGAGAAAGUACCGAGAAAAAUAUUGUACUUUCAAUGAUGAUAUUCAAGGGACAGCUGCAGUAGCUCUAGCAGGUCUUCUUGCAGCACAAAAAGUUAUUAGUAAACCAAUCUCCGAACACAAAAUCUUAUUCCUUGGAGCAGGAGAGGCUGCUCUUGGAAUUGCAAAUCUUAUAGUUAUGUCUAUGGUAGAAAAUGGCCUGUCAGAACAAGAGGCACAAAAGAAAAUCUGGAUGUUUGACAAGUAUGGUUUAUUAGUUAAGGGACGGAAAGCAAAAAUAGAUAGUUAUCAGGAACCAUUUACUCACUCAGCCCCAGAGAGCAUACCUGAUACUUUUGAAGAUGCAGUGAAUAUACUGAAGCCUUCAACUAUAAUUGGAGUUGCAGGUGCUGGCCGUCUUUUCACUCCUGAUGUAAUCAGAGCCAUGGCCUCUAUCAAUGAAAGGCCUGUAAUAUUUGCAUUAAGUAAUCCUACAGCACAGGCAGAGUGCACGGCUGAAGAAGCAUAUACACUUACAGAGGGCAGGUGUUUGUUUGCCAGUGGCAGUCCAUUUGGGCCAGUGAAACUUACAGAUGGGCGAGUCUUUACACCAGGUCAAGGAAACAAUGUUUAUAUUUUUCCAGGUGUGGCUUUAGCUGUUAUUCUCUGUAACACCCGGCAUAUUAGUGACAGUGUUUUCCUAGAAGCUGCAAAGGCCCUGACAAGCCAAUUGACAGAUGAAGAGCUAGCCCAAGGGAGACUUUACCCACCGCUUGCUAAUAUUCAGGAAGUUUCUAUUAACAUUGCUAUUAAAGUUACAGAAUACCUAUAUGCUAAUAAAAUGGCUUUCCGAUACCCAGAACCUGAAGACAAGGCCAAAUAUGUUAAAGAAAGAACAUGGCGGAGUGAAUAUGAUUCCCUGCUGCCAGAUGUGUAUGAAUGGCCAGAAUCUGCAUCAAGCCCUCCUGUGAUAACAGAAUAGAAGCACUCCCCUGAUAAAUACUUUCUGUGCUCCAGGGAACCCCUUUUUUCAGACAAGAAGAGAUAAUGUCUUCAGUUUUAUGGUGUUUUCUGUGUUUUGUUCUCCCUGACCACUUUGGUUGAUGUAUUUUUUCCAUGCGUCUCCACAUCUGUUGGGGUAGACGUGUUGAUUGAUUGCAUUGCCCACCAGCACCCUACAGUCAGAUAGUUGUGAUGCUUUAAUUCUAACAUACAGCCCGUACCACAUCCAGGAGAUGUAAAAAGUGUGUUUGUGAAUGUCUUCACUUGUACUCUAAUUCAGACUUGCCAAAGUAUUUGCUAUUUACUAUUAUGGGUAAUACUCUUCUCUGGCCUAGUUCUUACAGAGCUACUAAAAUAGAAAUUUACUUUUAUGGAUAGAAGUACAGAAUUUUGAGAAGAAACUAAAUUUUCACCAAAUUUUAAGGAAAAAUUGUCAUUAUCUAAAAAUGUUCUUAUAUAUCUGCUUCAUCUUACCUUCAUACUCUGAAAUUCCCUAUAGCAGACAGAGCUAGGGAAAUAUUAAAAAUUUACCCUAUUUAUUUUCUGGAACUAAAUCAAGCCUUAACUAUAACAUUAUGAGAGUAAUGGGAACUACUGCUGGCUUUAAGUAAAUAAAAGUCAUUGUUUUCAACAGUGUAUAAAAAUCAUAGUGUAACCUUUUUAUUUAAUAAAUAUCUUACAUUUAAUUGCUUCAGUUAUGCUAUCUUAUUGCCCAACUAGAAAUUUAGAUUUGCUUAUGAAAAACACAUAUUUUUGUUACUUCUAGAUGAUUCUAGGAGGGAGUAUAAGAUACCUAAUCAUAUGGGAACAUCACGUGACUUUUUAAAUCUAAAUUAGUCAUGCUUCACAUCAAAAUGAGUCAUAUUUAACUGGAGAAACUAUGCCCUUAUUCCAGAACUGAUGCUCUUUAUUGCUUGAGAUAAUUUUGGAAUGUUACUAUGAUACUGUUUCUUUGAAUAUCAUUAGUAGUGACAACUCUUUCUCCAUUGAAGGCAGACUUAAUUUUUUUAAACCACCAACAUUAAUUUAGAGCUAAAUGGGGAUGAAUAAGGUUGGUGUUCAUCUGGGAAAUGCCUUUUUUAAUCCCAGUAAAAUGGGUAAUAAUGGCUAUCCAGAACAGUUUUCUUGUGUGGCUUGCAUAUUGAAGAAUUCUAAAGGAAAAUAUAUCUGCCUACCAUGCUUGCUCUUAGGGAAGAAAACUUAAAUGCUCAUUCUAGGAUAGUAACAACAACAGAUAAUUCAUCGAUAAUAUGAGCAUGCACAGUAUUUGAUAUUGCUCUGUAGGAAAAAAGAGACUUCAUUUUUUUCAUCUUCUGCCUAUGAAUACAAAUUGAUUCUUUUUUUUUUUUUUUUUUUUUGAGACAGAGUCUCACUCUGUUACCAGGCUGGAGUGCAGUGGUGUGAUCUCAGCUCACUGCAACCUCUGCCUCCCAGGUUCAAGCAGUUCUCCUGCCUCAGCCUCCCAAGUAGCUGGGACUACAGGUACACGCCACCACGCCCAGCUAAUUUUUGUAUUUUUAGUAGAGACGGGAUUUCACCAUGUUGGCCAGGAGGGUCUCGAUUUCCUGACCUCGCGAUCCGCCCACCUCAGCCUUCCAAAGUGCUGGGAUUACAGGCGUGAGCCACCGCACCCAGCCAAUUUUUUUUUUUUUUUUUUUUGAGACAGAGUCUCGCUUUUGUCGCCCAGUCUGGAGUGUAGUGGCAUGAUCUCUGCAACCUCUGCCUCCUCGGUUCAGGCGAUUCUUCUGCCUUAGCCUCCCAAGUAGCUGGGAUUACAGGCACCGGCCACCACACCCAGCUAAUUUUUGUAUUUUUAGUAGAGAUGGGGUUUCACCAUGUUGGCCAGGCUGGUCUCAAAAUCCUGACUUCAGGUGAUCCACCCACUUUGGCCUCCCAAAGUGCUGGGAUUACAGGCGUGAGCCACCACACCUGGUCCAAUUCAUCAUAAUUCUGAAUAUAAUUUAAUAAUUUUAAAAUGGUCGCAAUGGCAUUGCCAUUUGGAGUAUGGGAAAAUGCAGUUGGUUAAUUCAUUGAACAGAUUAGUAAAGUCAGAAGUCUUUUUCAUAACAUACGGUCACAAUUCCUUUCUUUUAAUUAAAGACAAAAGGUUUAUGGGUUUUGGUUUGUUUGUUUUAGAUAUGGGGUUUUGCUAUGUCACCCUUGCUGGAGGGCGGUGGCUGUUCACAGGCGUGGGUCAUAGAGCACUGCAGCCUGGAACUCCUGGGUUCAAGCUCUCCUCCUGCCUCAGCCUCCUGAGCAGCUUGGACUAAAGGUGUGCACCACCGCACCUGGCUGAGAGGCUUCUGUUUUUCAUGUUCCCUUUAUCAAAACAAAAUCACGCCUAAACAUACUCUCUGUGUGAAAUCUUGAUUUUAGUUCAACCUAAGAAAUAUAAUAAAUAUAAACCUGUUUCUUGCUUAGUGUUUAUUGAAGGCAGGAACGUAUGCUGAAUUAAAGUAAUUUUACUACGAAGUUUGCUUAUUAAGUAUGCCUGGUACAGUCUUCAUGGAAGUUAUUAAGUAUUUUAAGGAAAAAAAUAGGCUAAAUGGCAUAUAGCCUGCUUAAAUAAAAUAAUUCUAUUUUUUUAAAAAGCUCCCAAUUGUCAUUGUUAUUUACCAGUCAAUCUUUCAACAAGUAUCAAUUAUUGGAUGUAAAUUAAAGUAAAAUUGCUUAAUAUUUAAGCUAAGAAUACAGGAAGGACUAUGAGCAUUGAGGAAAUCGGGGGAGGCCAGAAUGGCAUCAAGCUGGAAAAGAAAUUAAAACAUUACCUUCGAUGAGACUUUACCUAGCAAGAAGGUAAUUAUUUUGAAUAACAGCAAUAGAGAAUCUUUUAUUUUGAAUUGAGAAGAAAUUCUGAUGAUUAGAGUGUCAGUAAGUAGUAGGAAAAGGUAAGAAUACAUGUGUUUCUAAUCUCCCACCACCACCUGUUGUAUGGAACAAAUUGGAUUACUAGCAAGGGUAAGGUUUAUUGACAAUGAGAAGUUUUAGUCCAAGAUUUUAGUUAAAAUAUUUUAAAAUUUUUUGAUUCAUAACCAAGAAGUUGCCUCAGAUCACUGUGAAGCUUUAAAAUGCAGGUGCCUUUGCUCCUCCUCCCUCCAGGCCCCCGGGGGCAGAGCCCUGGCUGGUGUCUCUUCAGGAGGACCCCUGACACACCGAUUCUGCCCUCACAAUCACUGCCUUAAAGCAGGCAGCAGAAUCUUUUGGAGAACUAACAAGAUUCUGAUGCUGAUGCAUAGGGCCUGGGGUGGGGCCUCAGAUUCUGCUUUUUUUUUUUUUUUUUUUUUUUUUUUUAAACAGGGUCUCUUUCUUUUUCCUUUCUCACUCAGGCUGCAGUGAGUGGCGUGAUCUUGGCUCACUGCAACCUCCACUUCCUGGGCUCAAACGAUCCUCCCGCCUCAGCCUCCUGAGUAGCUGGGACUAUAGGCGCAAGUCUAUGCAACCACCCAGCUAAUUUUUGUAUUUUUAGAAGAGUGGGGGUUUUGCCACGUUGCCUGGGCUGGUCUCGAACUCCUGACCUCAAGUGAUCCAACCACCUCAGCCUCCCAAAGUGCUGGAAUUACAGGCAUGAGCCACUGCACCCAGCCAAGAAUGUCCACUUCUGACAAGCUCCCAGGUGAUGCCUAUGCUGCUGGUACAGUGAACAACAUGCUGAGAGGCAUUGCUCCAGGAUACUGCAUGUAGUGAGCAGUUCUUUAGCGUUUAUGUGUCAUAUACUUCAAGUUACAUGAAAAAGAUCAACUGAAAUUAUGUUCUUACACAGAAUAGUUUUCAUCUAGUUUUAUUAUGUUUUUACAGGCUGUUUACAAGAACAAAAAUAGAGAAUUUUUGAACAUAUUUUUCUGAAAACAUAAAAACUAGAGUACUCUUUAAUUCUAAAUUAUAGAUUUGUAGCAUACUUAGUAAACUUAGUAACCAAUUUUCAUUUGUAAAAGAUUAGCUAUCAAAUGGACAUUUAUUUCUCUUAGUUUUCUUAUGACAUGACUUGCCUUAUAUCCUUUGUCCUUUUUCUGUAACUUGUCAGCCUCUGGAGAAAUAGGAUUUUACAUUUUUGCAAAUGAGUUGCCAAUGAAUUAAGAUCAAAACGUCAUUAUUAAGGAGUAUGAAGCAUUAUUUACUGGCUCUCAGAUAACAGAAAACCCAAAAGGGAUGGUGGCGGAGUGAAGAAAGCCUUGCCUUGGGAAAAAUACUUCAAAUGCUCCCAUAGUUUUUUUUCCUCAAGCCCAGUCAGUAUCCUUCAAGGAUAACUUUUUCAUACCUUUUUUUUGGUUUGUUUGUUUCUGCUAGCUUUAUGACAGAGGUUAUAAUAUUCUUUUCUCCUCUCUUCUUUGACGUGUUACGUUGUCUUUUUUUUUUUUUUUUUAACUUCUUCAUACUCUUAAAAAGCUCCAGAAUGGCCAGGCGCAGUGGCUCACGCCUAUAAUCCCAGCACUUUGGGAGGCCAAGGCAGGCGGAUCACGAGGUCAGGAGAUCAAGACCAUCCUGGCUGACACGGUGAAACCCUGUCUCUACUAAAAAUACAAAAACUUAGCCAGGCGUGGUGGCGGGCGCCUGUAGUCCCAGGUACUCGGGAGUCUGAGGAGUGAACCCGGGAGGUGGAGGUUGCAGUGAGCUGAGAUCGCACCGCUGCACUCCAGCCUGGGCGACAGAGUGAGCCUCCAUCUCAAAAAAAAAAAAAAAAAAAAAAAAAAAAAAAAAAAAAUCUCCAGGGUUCUGUUGAAUUCACCAAAAUGGGGUCAGCUCUGGUGAGCCUAUGUAAUACUCGAGAACAUUAAUAUAAACCCAUAGCUCUUUACUGGGCUUCCAUUUAAAGGGAAGUCCUAAGAAUGAAAUGGCACCAGCAUCCUGUUUCCAUCCAAGACAAGACCACACGUGUUCAGGUGCCAUGUAUUCAUAUAGCUCUCAACUGAUUGGUGAUUUGCACUUUGUGCAUCUAAUUAUUAAAAUGAAACUCUCUACAGGUGAGCUGAAGUAACAUACUUCAUAUUUAAAAAGUUCACAGCAAUUUGACCAUAGAAAACUUUCUCAUCUGAAAUCAGGGUAAGUUUUUUUAAUGUAAGCAGAGAAAAAAAUAAAGCAGUGUUUUAUUUCAAAUUUCAGUAAGUUCAGGUGGGCCUAAUUAAGACAUGACUAUUAUUACAAAUCCUAUUCUUGCCAGAAGUUACUUAGAUAGAUUAGUGAUUAGAUUUUAAAAACAUUAUUUUCCUUUCUUGAAUAAGGAAAAUUGUGCAUCUCAAAGAGAAAAGUAAAUAUGGAAAUAUGUUCAUAGUUCAGUUGCAUAAAAUAGACACAUUAAGUCAAGUGAUUUGAAUGCUUAGUGUCUUUUGGUAAACAGCAUUUUGUCAACAAACUUUUCAUAUGGCUAUAGAAUCUUGUUUUUUCCAAAUAAAAACUUUGCAAUUGGGAGUUAUUCCUCCAUUCAGCACACUUUUUAAUGUUAAGACUAGGGGAAACUUGUGGGUAUAUAUUCAGUGGUUUUCAGGAUUUUCUUUUAUGUUCUAGAAAAGUAAUUUUUCCUUUCCUAGUUUUAAGUAUAUAUUCAAGCAAAUCGUUGAUUCCUAUACAGCCAUUGGAUUAUCACCAACACAUUUGGUAUAUACAGUGGGCCGAUAAUGACAAACUAAAGUUUGUGGUUAAUACCUACUCUAUACCAGACACUGUUCUAAGGAUCCGACAUAUUUAAUCCUCUGUUUACCCUCUGUUUCUGUGCCUGAUUUACAGACAGAGACAGAGGCACAGAGAGGUUAAAUGACUUGUCAAAGGUCUUAUGAUGUGUGGCAGAGCCUGGGUUUUUAGCUCAAACCCCUCUCAGUGAAGAAAGCCUUCUGUGUAGGCAAUUUCAUCUAAUACCUUCAUGAAUUGUUACUUCAGAUGAGAAUUCUCACUUAUUCUUUUUUUUUUUUUUUUUUCUUUUCUUUGAGACAGCCUUGCUCUGUCUCCCAGGCUGGAGUGCAGUGGCGCAAUCUCAGCUCACUGCAAGCUCCGCCUCCCGGGUUAUGCCAUUCUCCUGCCUCAGCCUUCCGAGUAGCUCGGACUACAGGCGCCCGCCACCUCGCCCAGCUAAUUUUUUGUAUUUUUAGUAGAGACGGGGUUUCACCGUGUUAGCCAGGAUGGUCUCGAUCUCCUGACCUCAUGAUCCACCCGCCUCGGCCUCCCAAAGUGCUGGGAUUACAGGCGUGAGCCACCGCGCCCGGCCUCACUUAGUCUUUUACCAGUUCAUCUGAUUUUUACUUUGUUCCCAUUUAUAAUUCAAAUAUAAUAUAAACGUCUUAUUCAUUUAGUCUUCAGCAUUUUAAGUAUUCGACACGAACAUUAAAGAUUUGGUGUUGAAUUUAAUAAAUUACACCAAAAAGUCUCAGUAGCCAAUUCACUAACAUCUUUUGAUUUGGUAAUCUUCACAGAAUCAACAACUGUUAACACUUCUGUGCAAAUAAAUUUCAGUUGUGCUUAUAUAUUAUAAUAUUCACUUUAGGAAUCCACCUGUCAAUUUGCAAUUCAAUUAUAAGGUAUAUUUUAAGUGAUAUCUAUGUAUUGUAUACACAUAUUCCAUUGAAAGGUGAGAAUAAUUAGAAAGUAGUAAUAUAAAAAUGUGUAUGAAAUAAGAACUUUCUUAAAAGACCUAGUUUAGCUAAAUAUAUGACAAUAUAAAAUGUCUGCCCAAUGUUUUAUUAUACUUUGUCUAAUGACCUUUAAAUUUAACUGAAAUUAAAACCGUACUUUUGCAGUUGAUAUUUUUGUGUUCCCUUUGUUAACAUACCAAGCACUAAUUAUUGACUUCAAGGAAGCCACGUAUUGCAAGUCAUUGCUUAGCCUUUCACAUCUGAGUGUUGAUAAGAUGACGGAAUGGGUAGUCUUGUAGUAAUUGCUUAUGGGAAUGCUAGUUUAAGAGGAAUGCCUUGUAUAGAACAUAUUAUACCAGAUUGACUUGUUAAAAAUGGUUCCAAGAAUCAGUCUAAAAACUUCAGAAUUAUGUGAAUUAUUUUUUCUCUGUUGUGAUAUGUUGUAAUGAGAUGUGUGUUCUUAUAUUUUCUUAGUAAAAUUUUCUUAAGCAUAAAA